GAGUUUGCCUGCCUCUCCAGAGAAAGAUGGUCAUGAGGCCCCUGUGGAGUCUGCUUCUCUGGGAAGCCCUACUUCCCAUUACAGUUACUGGUGCCCAAGUGCUGAGCAAAGUCGGGGGCUCGGUGCUGCUGGUGGCAGCGCGUCCCCCUGGCUUCCAAGUCCGUGAGGCUAUCUGGCGAUCUCUCUGGCCUUCAGAAGAGCUCCUGGCCACGUUUUUCCGAGGCUCCCUGGAGACUCUGUACCAUUCCCGCUUCCUGGGCCGAGCCCAGCUACACAGCAACCUCAGCCUGGAGCUCGGGCCGCUGGAGUCUGGAGACAGCGGCAACUUCUCCGUGUUGAUGGUGGACACAAGGGGCCAGCCCUGGACCCAGACCCUCCAGCUCAAGGUGUACGAUGCAGUGCCCAGGCCCGUGGUACAAGUGUUCAUUGCUGUAGAAAGGGAUGCUCAGCCCUCCAAGACCUGCCAGGUUUUCUUGUCCUGUUGGGCCCCCAACAUCAGCGAAAUAACCUAUAGCUGGCGACGGGAGACAACCAUGGACUUUGGUAUGGAACCACACAGCCUCUUCACAGACGGACAGGUGCUGAGCAUUUCCCUGGGACCAGGAGACAGAGAUGUGGCCUAUUCCUGCAUUGUCUCCAACCCUGUCAGCUGGGACUUGGCCACAGUCACGCCCUGGGAUAGCUGUCAUCAUGAGGCAGCACCAGGGAAGGCCUCCUACAAAGAUGUGCUGCUGGUGGUGGUGCCUGUCUCGCUGCUCCUGAUGCUGGUUACUCUCUUCUCUGCCUGGCACUGGUGCCCCUGCUCAGGAUGCCCUGCCCCUGAAAGAACUACCCGACUGACCAGGGCUCCGUGGUCAUUUCCAUGCCAGGCUGUCGGAGCUGGCUUGUCCCAAGGUGGAGAAAGGGAGUCAGCAAGGAGGAGUCACUGAGCCCUCACUAUGGUGGGUGUGUCCCAGAAGGCAGGGUCUGGGUCCAGCCUCUAAGCAUGGGGACAGGCAAUGCUGAUUCCUGUUCAUUCUCUCCAGCAGAGAGAAGGGCAAGAGGGAACAGCUGAGCCUGCACUCCACCUGAAGGCCCCAUCUGCUGUGGGAGGGUAUUGCCCUGGCCCCUGGCCCCUGGCCCCUGCCCCAAGAGUCCCCAGGAUUUGUGAUAAGAAAGUGGAAGCCAGGAAAACAGCAGGGAAAAAAUACCUUUAUUGAGAUAUAAUUCACAUAGCAUACAAUUCACCUAUUUAAAGUAUACAAUUCGAUGCCUUUUAGUGUAUUCGCAGAGUUGGGCAUCCACCUUCACAACCAAUUUUAAAACAUUUCUAUUACCUCCCCCAAAACCCCAUAACCCCUUAGCCAUCACCUCCCAAAUCCCCCAUUCCUCCCACAGCACUAGUCUGCUUUCUGCCUCUAUGCUUUUGUCUUUCCUGGACAUUUCAUAUAAAUAGAACUAUACACUAUGUGGCCCUUUGGCCAGGCUUUUUUCACUUAGUGUCAUGUCCUCAAGGCUCAUAAAAUAGCAUCUUUGGCCACUGAGAAGGGACCCAACAACCUGGGAUAGUAGAAAGCUCCAUGCAGGGAGUCCAGAAGCUGGUUCUGGCUCUGCCUCAUGGCUUCUGUCCAGUGAUUUAACUGGGUCCACCACAGUCCUAACUUUCCAUACCUUCUACAAUUAAAUGUAUGGCAUAGUUGCAGGCCAAGGUUAGAUACUAGGAAGAAUUUCCUAUUCUUGAAGAGCCUCCCUUUCCAGGGUGUUGGAAGACCAGGAGAAAUGUUCCUUUACCUAAGGUGACCUUGGGCUAACACACUGAGGAUUCAGAGGCCUGCAGGCAGGCCAAGGAUUCCAAGACUCCAAACACUGGAGGGGUAACUUUCUUUCUGAUGUCCUUACCAGGGAAAAAGAAAAAGGAUGUCCAUGCUGACAGAGUGGGUCCAGAGACAGAGAACCCCCUUGUGCAGGAUCUGCCAUAAAGGACAAUAUGAACUGAUGCCUGGACUAUCAGUAACCCCACUGCACAGGCACACGAUGCUCUGGGACAUAACUGGUGCCUGGAAAUCACCAUGGUCCUCAUAUCUCCCAUGGGAAUCCUGUCCUGCCUCGAAGGAGCAGCCUGGGCAGCCAUCACACCACGAGGACAGGAAGCACCAGCACGUUUCACACCUCCCCCUUCCCUCUCCCAUCUUCUCAUAUCCUGGCUCUUCUCUGGGCAAGAUGAGCCAAGCAGAACAUUCCAUCCAGGACACUGGAAGUUCUCCAGGAUCCAGAUCCAUGGGGACAUUAAUAGUCCAAGGCAUUCCCUCCCCCACCACUAUUCAUAAAGUAUUAACCAACUGGCACCAAGGAAUUGCCUCCAGCCUGAGUCCUAGGCUCUAAAAGAUAUUACAUAUUUGAACUAAUAGAGGAACUCUGAGUCACCCAUGCCAGCAUCAGCUUCAGCCCCAGACCCUGCAGUUUGAGAUCUGAUGCUUCCUGAGGGCCAAGGCAUUGCUGUAAGAAAAGGUCUAGAAAUAGGUGAAAGUGAGAGGUGGGGGACAGGGGUUUCUCUUUCUGGCCUAAGGACUUUCAGGUAAUCAGAGUUCAUGGGCCCUCAAAGGUAAAUUGCAGUUGUAGACACCGAGGAUGGUUGACAACCCAUGGUUGAGAUGGGCACCGUUUUGCAGGAAACACCAUAUUAAUAGACAUCCUCACCAUCUCCAUCCGCUCUCACGCCUCCUGCAGGAUCUGGGAGUGAGGGUGGAGAGUCUUUCCUCACGCUCCAGCACAGUGGCCAGGAAAAGAAAUACUGAAUUUGCCCCAGCCAACAGGACGUUCUUGCACAACUUCAAGAAAAGCAGCUCAGCUCAGGAUGAGUCUUCCUGCCUGAAACUGAGAGAGUGAAGAACCAUAAAACGCUAUGCAGAAGGAACAUUAUGGAGAGAAAGGGUACUGAGGCACUCUAGAAUCUGCCACAUUCAUUUUCAAAUGCAAAUGCAGAAGACUUACCUUAGUUCAAGGGGAGGGGACAAAGACCCCACAGCCCAACAGCAGGACUGUAGAGGUCACUCUGACUCCAUCAAACUUUUUAUUGUGGCCAUCUUAGGAAAAUACAUUCUGCCCCUGAAUGAUUCUGUCUAGAAAAGCUCUGGAGUAUUGAUCACUACUGGAAAAACACUUAAGGAGCUAAACUUACCUUCGGGGAUUAUUAGCUGAUAAGGUUCACAGUUUCUCUCACCCAGGUGUAACUGGAUUUUUUCUGGGGCCUCAAUCCAGUCUUGAUAACAGCGAGGAAAGAGGUAUUGAAGAAACAGGGGUGGGUUUGAAGUACUAUUUUCCCAGGGUGGCUUCAAUCUCCCCACCUAGGAUGUCAGCCCUGUCCAAGGACCUUCCCUCUUCUCCCCAGUUCCUGGGCAAUCACUUCACCUUGGACAAAGGAUCAGCACAGCUGGCCUCCAGAUCCACAUCACCACUCUUCCACUCGAUUGUUCCCAGAUCCUCCCUGCCUGGCCUGCUCAGAGGUUCCCUGUUGGUAACCUGGCUUUAUCAAAUUCUCAUCCCUUUCCCACACCCACUUCUCUCCUAUCACCUUCCCCCAAGAUUACCUGAACAGGGUCCAUGGCCACUCAACCUGUCAGCUUGCACCAUCCCCACCUGCCACCUACAGUCAGGCCACAUGCCUGGUCACUGAAUCAUGCAAAACUGGCCUCAGUCCCUAAAAAUGAUGUGGAAAGGAAAGCCCAGGAUCUGACAAUGAGCCCUGGUGGAUUUGUGGGGAAAAAAUACACAGCACUCCCCACCUUUCUUUCGUUCAUCUCCAGGGCCCCACCUCAGAUCAAAGCAGCUCUGGAUGAGAUGGGACCUGCAGCUCUCCCUCCACAAGGUGACUCUUAGCAACCUCAUUUCGACAGUGGUUUGUAGCGUGGUGCACCAGGGCCUUGUUGAACAGAUCCACACUGCUCUAAUAAAGUUCCCAUCCUUAAUGA